AGAUCUCUUCUCAUAAGGGCACUGUGUGGAGCUUCUGAGAUCUGUGGAGGUUUUUCUCUGCAAAUGCAGGAAGAAAUCAGGUGGAUGGAUGCAUAAUUAUGGCCCUGCUCCUGGUCUCUUUGCUGGCAUUCCUGAGCUUGGGCUCAGGAUGUCAUCAUCGGAUCUGUCACUGCUCUAACAGGGUUUUUCUCUGCCAAGAGAGCAAGGUGACAGAGAUUCCUUCUGACCUCCCGAGGAAUGCCAUUGAACUGAGGUUUGUCCUCACCAAGCUUCGAGUCAUCCAAAAAGGUGCAUUUUCAGGAUUUGGGGACCUGGAGAAAAUAGAGAUCUCUCAGAAUGAUGUCUUGGAGGUGAUAGAGGCAGAUGUGUUCUCCAACCUUCCCAAAUUACAUGAAAUUAGAAUUGAAAAGGCCAACAACCUGCUCUACAUCAACCCUGAGGCCUUCCAGAACCUUCCCAACCUUCAAUAUCUGUUAAUAUCCAACACAGGUAUUAAGCACCUUCCAGAUGUUCACAAGAUUCAUUCUCUCCAAAAAGUUUUACUUGACAUUCAAGAUAACAUAAACAUCCACACAAUUGAAAGAAAUUCUUUCGUGGGGCUGAGCUUUGAAAGUGUGAUUCUAUGGCUGAAUAAGAAUGGGAUUCAAGAAAUACACAACUGUGCAUUCAAUGGAACCCAACUAGAUGAGCUGAAUCUAAGCGAUAAUAAUAAUUUAGAAGAAUUGCCUAAUGAUGUUUUCCACGGAGCCUCUGGACCAGUCAUUCUGAACAGAAGGACCAGGACUCCUACAGAACCAAAUGUCCUAUUAGCCAAAUAUCCAUCUGGCCAAGGUGUGUUGGAGGAACCGGAGUCUCUCUCCUCAUCCAUAGAUAUUUCAAGAACAAGGAUCCAUUCCCUGCCUAGCUAUGGCUUAGAAAAUCUUAAGAAGCUGAGGGCCAGGUCGACUUACAACUUAAAAAAGCUGCCUACUCUGGAAAAGCUUGUCGCCCUCAUGGAAGCCAGCCUCACCUAUCCCAGCCAUUGCUGUGCCUUUGCAAACUGGAGACGGCAAAUCUCUGAGCUUCAUCCAAUUUGCAACAAAUCUAUUUUAAGGCAAGAAGUUGAUUAUAUGACUCAGGCUAGGGGUCAGAGAUCCUCUCUGGCAGAAGACAAUGAGUCCAGCUACAGCAGAGGAUUUGACAUGACGUACACUGAGUUUGACUAUGACUUAUGCAAUGAAGUGGUUGACGUGACCUGCUCCCCUAAGCCAGAUGCAUUCAACCCAUGUGAAGAUAUCAUGGGGUACAACAUCCUCAGAGUCCUGAUAUGGUUUAUCAGCAUCCUGGCCAUCACUGGGAACAUCAUAGUGCUAGUGAUCCUAACUACCAGCCAAUAUAAACUCACAGUCCCCAGGUUCCUUAUGUGCAACCUGGCCUUUGCUGAUCUCUGCAUUGGAAUCUACCUGCUGCUCAUUGCAUCAGUUGAUAUCCAUACCAAGAGCCAAUAUCACAACUAUGCCAUUGACUGGCAAACUGGGGCAGGCUGUGAUGCUGCUGGCUUUUUCACUGUCUUUGCCAGUGAGCUGUCAGUCUACACUCUGACAGCUAUCACCUUGGAAAGAUGGCAUACCAUCACGCAUGCCAUGCAGCUGGACUGCAAGGUGCAGCUCCGCCAUGCUGCCAGUGUCAUGGUGAUGGGCUGGAUUUUUGCUUUUGCAGCUGCCCUCUUUCCCAUCUUUGGCAUCAGCAGCUACAUGAAGGUGAGCAUCUGCCUGCCCAUGGAUAUUGACAGCCCUUUGUCACAGCUGUAUGUCAUGUCCCUCCUUGUGCUCAAUGUCCUGGCCUUUGUGGUCAUCUGUGGCUGCUAUAUCCACAUCUACCUCACAGUGCGGAACCCCAACAUCGUGUCCUCCUCUAGUGACACCAGGAUCGCCAAGCGCAUGGCCAUGCUCAUCUUCACUGACUUCCUCUGCAUGGCACCCAUUUCUUUCUUUGCCAUUUCUGCCUCCCUCAAGGUGCCCCUCAUCACUGUGUCCAAAGCAAAGAUUCUGCUGGUUCUGUUUCACCCCAUCAACUCCUGUGCCAACCCCUUCCUCUAUGCCAUCUUUACCAAAAACUUUCGCAGAGAUUUCUUCAUUCUGCUGAGCAAGUGUGGCUGCUAUGAAAUGCAAGCCCAAAUUUAUAGGACAGAAACUUCAUCCACUGUCCACAACACCCAUCCAAGGAAUGGCCACUGCUCUUCAGCUCCCAGAGUCACCAGUGGUUCCACUUACAUACUUGUCCCUCUAAGUCAUUUAGCCCAAAACUAAAACACAAUGUGAAAAUGUAUCUGAGUAUUGAAUGAUAAUUCAGUCUUGCCUUUGAAGGGUAUGUCACAAAGAGCUGACAGUGCUUCUACACAUUUCAUCUAAUUUAAUAUUCCUGGCAUACCUUUAAGGUAAAUUGGUCAGGAACUAUUAAUUCCAUGUGAUACAUUAGGAAGCUGAAUUAUUAGUAACAACAAUAAUAAUUAAAGAAUGCAAUACUGUAUUACAUAUUUUAUCCUUAUAUAUGUUAUUUUUGCACGUUAUGUUCAAAGUGCUUUUGUUCAGAUAUCUCAAGUGAUCCCUGUUAAAUAAGCAGGACAGGGAUUAUUCUUGGAGUUUUACAAAUGAGGAAACCACGACUCAAAGAGUUAAGUGACUUGUUCAAAAUUGUUUAGUUUGUAAGAGGCAGAGCCAGGAUUAGGUAUUCCGACUCCCAGAGAAUUUCCCAGAGAAGCACCAUGGUAUUCAUUCAUUCAUUCAUUCAACAAAUAUUAAUUGAACACCCAUCUGAAGCCUUUGUAAUGCGUCAGUGUGGAUAGGCUGAAAUACAUUUCCCAGAUUUCCCUUCCUCAUGUGUUU